ACGCAAUUGCACACCAACGCUAGGGGAUGAUCUCGCCCCAGCUGACUCAUUUUCUCAUUCGUGCAGCAGACAUUUAUUGAGCGCCUACUGUAUGGAUGGAUACUGUACGCCAGAGAACCGCUGCGUGGCGCUCCAAUUCAGUUCUUCACAUCCACACAGCCCUGGAGGAUUUACAAAAUACAUUAAGUGAGCAGCAUAGAAGAAAUAAUGCCUUUUGAGGGACAGUUGCAUUUAACAGACAGCCUUACUAAGGCAAGAGUUCUGGAGCCGCCACUGCACUCCAGCCGGCCUUGGCUUCUGAGCUUUGGAUUCUGGGCAGUAAUGGUCACAUUCCCAGCGUCCUGGAAAAGCUUGCCCUUGGCUUCUGGCCCUGACUCUGCCUCCCACUGACUAGUGGACGUCACUGCCCCUCUCUGGGCCUGGCAACACCAUCCUGUUCAAUGAGGCUGCGGCUGGAUCAGAGGUCCCCAGGCCUGGAACCUUCCAGGGCUGGGCUCAGCUCCCCACCCCAUCCCCCAGACGACUUACAGUGACAAAGGGGCAAAGCCUGAGAGAGGCCGAUUCCUCCACUUCCACUCUGUGACCUUCUGGGUUGGCAACGCCAAGCAGGCCACGUCAUUCUACUGCAGCAAGAUGGGCUUUGAACCUCUAGCCUACAGGGGCCUGGAGACCGGUUCCCGGGAGGUGGUCAGCCAUGUAAUCAAACAAGGGAAGAUUGUGUUUGUCCUCUCCUCAGCGCUCAACCCCUGGAACAAAGAGAUGGGCGAUCACCUGGUGAAACACGGUGACGGAGUGAAGGACAUUGCGUUCGAGGUGGAAGAUUGUGACUACAUCGUGCAGAAAGCACGGGAACGGGGCGCCAAAAUCAUGCGGGAGCCCUGGGUAGAGCAAGACAAGUUUGGGAAGGUGAAGUUUGCUGUGCUGCAGACGUAUGGGGACACCACACACACCCUGGUGGAGAAGAUGAACUACAUCGGCCAAUUCUUGCCUGGAUAUGAGGCCCCAGCGUUCAUGGACCCCCUACUUCCUAAACUGCCCAAAUGCAGUCUGGAGAUGAUCGACCACAUUGUGGGAAACCAGCCUGAUCAGGAGAUGGUGUCCGCCUCCGAAUGGUACCUGAAAAACCUGCAGUUCCACCGCUUCUGGUCCGUGGAUGACACGCAGGUGCACACGGAAUAUAGCUCUCUGCGAUCCAUUGUGGUGGCCAACUAUGAAGAGUCCAUCAAGAUGCCCAUCAAUGAGCCAGCGCCUGGCAAGAAGAAGUCCCAGAUCCAGGAAUAUGUGGACUAUAACGGGGGCGCUGGGGUCCAGCACAUCGCUCUCAAGACCGAAGACAUCAUCACAGCGAUUCGCCACUUGAGAGAGAGAGGCCUGGAGUUCUUAUCUGUUCCCUCCACGUACUACAAACAACUGCGGGAGAAGCUGAAGACGGCCAAGAUCAAGGUGAAGGAGAACAUUGAUGCCCUGGAGGAGCUGAAAAUCCUGGUGGACUACGACGAGAAAGGCUACCUCCUGCAGAUCUUCACCAAACCGGUGCAGGACCGGCCCACGCUCUUCCUGGAAGUCAUCCAGCGCCACAACCACCAGGGUUUUGGAGCCGGCAACUUCAACUCACUGUUCAAGGCUUUCGAGGAGGAGCAGAACCUGCGGGGUAACCUCACCAACAUGGAGACCAAUGGGGUGGUGCCCGGCAUGUAAGCCCCGCCCACCCCACGGAGGCCACAGCCACACAGCCACGCCCCCUGAUUCUGGAACUCGCCCAACUUCCCUACUGGCUGCUCCCCUUGGGUCCCGCCCACCAGCGGACUCGGCCCCCAAGGCUCCGCCCACACUGACCACGCCCCUCGGCGGGGCCGCCCUCUGCUCCAGCCCUCCCGAUUAAAGCGUGCCCCGGUCCAA